CUCCUCGCCUUUUCUCUCGUGCGUGACAAGAGCCGCAAAAAUGUGGGUCCGCGCGAGCGCUGCGCGGCGCCCCCACCCCCGGGCAGGGAGGUGGCGAGCGCCGCGUGUUUAGACUGCGUGUGGCGGCCGGGAGCGGGAGCCGCACUCCAGGGCGCGGGCCGGGAGAGCGAAAGCCGCGGGCGCCCCGGACGGCGGGCCAGGUGGCCGCGCCAUGUCCAUCGGUGGACGGGUUCGUAGGGCCUGCUCUGAGGUCGGUCGCUAGUGGGACAUCCCUUGUGUCCCCCAAGUGCCGCUUUCUGGAAACGGGGAAGUGUCAGCCUUGUUGUCAGUCGCUCCCCAUGGUCUCUUCUCACCCUCGCUCUCCUCUGCCAGUUCCGGAGAUGCAGUGGGCCGGAGAGAGUGGCGCUUGGGGCCAGAUAAUCUUUCUCACUGGGGUGACCGUGUGGCUCUGCUGUGAGUGCAGGUCGUGACUCCUUAGAGUUUAGUGCCUGAGCGUCGGGGGACAGGGCAGCAUCCUUAGGUGCAGUGCUUUCAGGAAAUGUGCAUCCAUGGAAGUAGGAAAUGCGUGUUUAUGUUGCCCAACCUAAAACAUCACACUUAAUGGGGUGAAUUUAUUAGGAACCACAGCCAGACUCAGCAGCACAGACAUUUUGAAAUGCUCCUAGGCUGGGCUGUAGGAUUGCGUUUUAAGUACAGGUAUAUAUUUUUUAAACACAACUAUGUUGAAGAAGGGAUGGGAAGGGGAGACAGCCGUGACAGAAGGUACGUUCUCAAAAACUCCUGGGGCUUAUGAUAAUAUAAAAAAGAUAGAGGCCCAGUUUACUAGGUGUUUUAAAAUGGUUUUGCUUUUUUGCAUGCUUUGAACUGCUUCCAUGAAAUAAUGGAGUUCUAGGAAAUAAUGCAUCUUAGGAAAGGUUGUUCUUCCCUCUAGCUAUGAAUUGCCCUAUGGGAUUUUAGAUAGCAUUUCCCACUUGAUGCUCCUUGCCCUCAUCACCAUUCAUCUUAUUACUACAGUCAGUUUCUGUGGACUACCAAGAUAAUAGCGCUUUCCCAAACACAAGCACUCAUUUUAAAGCAGUUAUCUUUUAAUGUGAAUUCUCUUUGUUAAAAUGUCAAUGUUGUGAGAUUUGGUAGCAUAUUCCUAUUUAAACUAGUGAAUAUGAUUUUGAUAUGAACCUUGAAAGAUGGGGAAUUUGAGUGCUUUUAACGUGUUGAAAGUGUAACACUUGAAACUUUGGAGGCUGGGAAAUCGAGGCGAUGAAGUGUUCUAUAAGAUAGGUUUUCUGCCCUUUUAAAUAUAGUGGUGCUGUCUUUGUUUCCAAUUGGAAUUUCAGUGUAAUGCACUGUUCUCACUUCAGAUGCAGAGGAAGGAUAAAAUAGUGAAGUUGAUAUGGCCCUGUUCAGCCAAAUUUCCGAAUCAUAAAGUGACAUGCUAAUAGGAUAUACUGUGGCAUUUCUGUGUAUUACAGCUUGUAUGGUUUGAGUUACUUUUCCACACAUAAUUUUUUCUCCUCCACACAAGUCAUUAAAUAUGUUUUCCUGAGAGAUAGUCAAGCUUUGUUGUAUAGGAAAGUUUCGUUUGUGGAAAUAAAUGAGUUUCACUGUAAGCUAAUGUAAUUCUAUUACGUGAGGAAAUGUUCCUUAAAAAAUAAAGAAUAUUAUAUACUGUUGUUUUCCUGAAUAUUUUUUAAAAGACACAUUAACUAUUUCCUAUUUAAUCCUUCAUGGACAUCCCACAAUAGAUUACCAGCACCUUAAAAAAAAAAAAAAAAACAAAAACGAAAAAACCAAAGACUAAAAACCCCCAUUGGGGUUUUUUUUUUGGUACAUACUUUGAAAUUUAUAUUUUAAAUGAAUUAAAAAGUAACACUUUUUAUAUGUACAUUGAAAGACAUAAAACUUGAUACAGAGAAAGUCAAAUUUUAAAUUGUUAAGGAUUAUCAAAUUGAAUUUGCCAUGUAGUUCACAGUUUCCAACAAAAUGUUUGUUUCAACAAGAAAAAAUUUGAAGUCAUUGGCAUACAUUUAGAGUUUACACUUUUCAUAAACCAAGCCAGCAUUUUUAUUAGCACGUCAGAAACUCCCAGUGAGAUUAAUAUUAAUUAAACAUAAUCAAAAACUGCAGAAUUACCUGCUUUUGAAUUAUCUCCCCAAGGAAAACUAGUCCAAUAAAAUAAAACUUGAAAAUUAUUAAUAUAAAAGAGAGGCCAGUCUGACUUAGUAAAACUCUGAAUGCUAGAAUUUUUAAUGAAGACAGAUUUAUUUGAAAGUAAAGAUGUAAACAUAAUGCAAAGAUAUAAACAUGGUUUGUAUUAUAUCUUUAUAGUUUAUAUCUUUACUAACAAGUAAAAUAAGGUAAUAAAAAUGUGUAACACAUGAUAAACCUAUGCUACAUAAAAUAGCAUAAACAUACUUUUUUCAUAUAUAAGAAUUACUUUGGGAGGUCCUUAAUGCUUUACUUUGGUUUGGAGAGAAAAUGUUUUAAAAUUGACUUUGCUUUACAAAUGAGAUCCUGAAAAAUAGCAACCAAAGAUAUUUUUUCUCAAAUGAAGUGGCCGUUUCAAAAUUAUAUUACAAAUUCUGAACUGAUUGGAUUAAUACCCUUUUACUAGUUUAGUUUUUCUAUUAUUGCCUGAAAAGCAUUUUUCUGCUUUAGAAAACAGUCCAGUUGACUUUUGAUUGUUCUGUGUUUUGAGGACGUAUCUUGAGUAAUUUAAGAAAUAAAGUGUUUUGGGUUUAAAAGCUCCCAUGUCUUAAGUUGGUGAAAUUUGAAAAGGUAUUUUUAAAAAGAGGGAUAUUCAGGGCUGGGUGCUGUGGCUCAUGCCUGUAAUCCCAACACUUUGGAAGACAGAGGCAGGAGGAUCGCUUGAACCCAGGAGUUGGAGACCAGCCUGGGCGACAUAGUCUGUACAAAACAAACAAACAAACAAACAAAAUUGGCUGGGCGUGGUGGUGUGCACCUGUAGUACUAGCUAUUUGGAAAGCUGAGACAGGAGAAUCGCUUCAGCCCAGAAGGUUGAGGCUGCAGUGAGCCAAGAUCACGCCACUGCACUCCAGCCUGGGCAACAGAGCAAGAGCCUGUCUUAAAAAAAAAAAAAAAAAAGGCGGGGGGGGAUAUUCAGAUUUGAAUGGUAAAUCCUGACUGAUUUAAUCCCUUGCCAACUGAGGAUAUUGAUUCCUAAGGGAAUCACUUAAAGUUUCUUCAUCUGAGUUAUGGAAUUUUUUAAAAAACAAAAACAAAUUUCCUCUCCAUUUUUUUAACUAGUUUUUAAAAUGUCUUGAACAUUAUUUUGACAUAAUCAAAUUGAGCAGUAUCAUUUGUAGAAUAAAUUGUUAAUUUUUUCUUUUAGAACAACAUUUUGGUAACUUGUUUUAAUGGAGGGAAGAAAGGUUGUGAAUAAAGUAUAGGACAAUGUUUUUUCAUUUAGAUUUGAAUAUAGGUGUGACCACUCAGAGGAUUCACUACAAAUGAAAUCAUCAGGCUUCAUUUAAGGAUUUGACUGAGGUGGACUUGGGAAGCUGUCCAUUUUCCACAUCUCGACUUUUGCUUAGUUGCUUGAUGUAACUCACUUCAUGCUGAGUUUAGACAGCUCUCACAGUUUCCUCAGCACCAGGUUAAACAGAACUAUCCUUUCAAAGAGCUUCCCUGCUGAGAUGCAGAGUAGGAGUAAAUAGAAGAGUGUGGGAUGUCCACAAAGCAAGGAAUUAAACAAAGUAGGCCAGACAGACUAUAGAGGGAGCUGCUUGUCUUUAAGAUUACUCUAAGGAACUCUGCCACUUCCUCUAGCUUAGUGAAUAUUUUGGUAGAUUGUUCUAGAUACUGUUAGCCAUGAAAUCAAGCUUUUCAACAUAAGGAAUUGAUAAUUCUGAAAUGCUAUAUAAGUUUAUGUAGAUGCUUAUCCAAUUAUAAAUAUAUUCUCAUUGUUUAUAUUUUAUAAAAUUAAAUAUAAGAAACUACCAGAAUAACCUUUUUUUUUUUUUUUGGUAAAUUGGAGUUAAAUUUGCAAUAAGAAUAAUUUUGAAAAUUAGCGUGUAUCAACAACUCAGGUUCAAAAGUUUCUCUAAUAGAAUCUGCUUUGUUCAUAGUCUGUUUUUUACUAAGCUAUUUAAAAAUAUUUUAAGAUCAUAUAACACCUAUUUGAUUACAAUUAUUGGAGAGAUUUUCAGGAACGCUAUGGAGAUGUAAUGACUCAUCACAAACAAAUUGGUCACUUUUUUUAAAGUAGGUAUUUGAAGCCCUGAGUAGCAAGUUGUUUUAGCUUUAAGUGCCUUAAGAACAGCUUUACUCUCCAGAAGCUCACAAUGUAGUAGAGAUGAUGGGCAUGUAAACGUAAGUCAAAUGCAGUAUGACUGGACUAUAGAAAUGUGUAUAAGACAAAGCAAGGAUUCAUUGGGAGACAUGUUCUAUAUCCAGGCAAAAAGGGGAGUCAGGGAAGACUUCGUGAAGGAAAUAUGGAUUAGUCAUGUUAAAGGAAUUUUUAAGGAACUUAAAAUUUCAGAUAGAGGAACAGCUACAAGGUAAUUGACAGAUGAAGACAACUGCUCUUUGCAGGGCAGUUUGGCAAUGUAUAUUAGAAUCCUUGAAGUGUUCUUUUUUGACCCAGUAAUUCUAGUUUUAGGGAUUUUAAUCUAUGAGCAUAAAUCUUUUGGCAAAUCUGGUUGUCUUUUGAAUCCGUCUACUUCUUUUCAUAAUCCAUCACCACCCUAAACUACUAGCAUUUUUGGUCAGGUUUACUACAGUAGCCUCCUAAUCUUGGUUUAUCCCAAUCUACUUUGUCCCCUUCUGAUCUGUUUCCUACACUGUAAUCAGAGGGAUCUUUUAAAAAUGCAAACCUGAUUACAUCACCCUACUGUUUGAUAUGCUUCAGUAGCUUUCCAUUGCAUUCAGGAUAUGGACAGAACUCUGUGUCUUAUAUGGUGGCAUCUGCCUGUCUUACAAGGUCUUGCAUAGUCUGGCCCUUACCUUUCUGUCUAGUCAUGACUUGAGCCAUGUUCUUGACUUACUCUUUUUGUUCCAGCCUUGUUGGCCUUAUCUCAGUCCCUUGUUCUUGCCAUGCUCCUUCCCACAGUGAGGGCUUUGUACCUGCCGUUGCCCCUGCUGAGAAUGUUUUUACUUUUCUUUCACCUAAACUUCGAUUUAUCUUUCCUCAGGGAAGGCUUCCCUAUCACAGACUCUCAGAGCACCAUGAACUCUCCUCAUAGCACUUGCUGUCAUUGUAAUUUCAUAUGUGUUGGAGAUUAACAUCUGUUUUUCCAAAUAGAUUGUAACCUCCAGAAAUCCUGAUAAUGUGUUUCUUUUUCCUCACCAUUAUAGAGUUAAUGCUUACCACAGUGCUUGAAACUCGUCUAUUAAUUCUUGGAACUCAUUUGUGGCAAGGAUUAAUAAAUAGAUGAUAAUCAUCACAGAGAACAACUCUAAGUGUUCAACAAUUGGCAAAUGGUUGCAUAAACUGGGUAUAUUCAUUUGGGAGGAUGUGUUUAAAACAUGUUGUAGAAGUAUGUGUAAUAACAUGGGAAAGUGCUGUCAUAUUAUGUGAAAAAAUUAGUUUACAAAAUAGUCACUUAUUAAAAGUGUGGAAAAAAAUACACCGAAGUAUAAAAGUUGGUUAUCUCUGGAAGGUAUGUUUUAUAUUUUCAGAUUUUUUACAGAUAACAUGUGCUGAUUUUAUAAUUUAAAAAAACCAUGUACAAAAUUAAGGAAAAAUUGAUUUUCUAGAUAUGGUUCCAGAAAUGUAGUGGGAGACAUGAGAUUCGUAAUGGUCUCCAAAAUAUGUGUCAACCAAAAUGCAUGAUUGCAUGAUGAUCAUAUUGAACUUAAUUAUAUAAAUUCCAUUUAGAAAUUGCAAAAUGAUUCAUAAAUUAAAGCAAGCCAGUAAUUUCUGGUUGUAUUAUUCUUACUUGUAUGUAAAGUGGUUUUAAUUUUAAAAUGUUUUGAAAAGUAACAUGGUUUUGGCACAUGACAGCACUAAAACAGAGUAAAGACUAGAAUUAACUUAAAUAUAUAUGAGAGCUUAAUAUAGGUUGAGCAUCCCUUAUCUAAAACUCCAUAAUCUGAAAUCCUUCAAAAUCUGAAAUGUUUUGAACACCAACAUGAUGCCACAAGUAGAAAAUUCCACACCUGACCUCAUGAUGGGUCGCAGUCAAAACUUCGUUUCAGGCUGGAUGCAGUGGCUCAUGUCUGUAAUCCCAACACUUUGGGAGGCUAAGGUGGGAGGAUUGCUUCAGCCCAGGAGUUCAAGACCAGCCUGGGCAACAUGGAAAGACGCUAUCUCUACAAAAAAAUACAAAAGUUAGCCAGGCAGGGUGGUACACGUUUGUGGUUCCAGCUACUUGGGAGGCUGAGGCAGGAGGAUCGCUUGAGCCCAGGAGGUGAAGGCUGCAGUGAGCCAUGAUUGUAUGACUGCAUUCCAGCCUGGGUGACAGAGCAAGUCCCUGUCUCAAAAACAAUCAAAACAACUUUGUUUCAUGUGUAACAUUAUUUAAAAUUAUAUAAAAUUACAUUCAGGUUUGGUCCCAUCCUCAGGAUAUCUCAUGUAUGUGCAAAUAUUCUAAAAUCUGAAACACUUCUGGUCCCAAGCAUUUCAGAUAAGGGGUAUUCAACUUGUAUAUGAAAAUGGAUCCCACCUUCAUUUAUGAGUAGGGAAAAGAAGAAUUGUUUAAUAAACAGUGUUGGGAUAGCCAGUUAGUCAUCUGGAAAAAUAAUGUUGGCUUCCAGAGGAGUUAAAGAUUUAAAUAUGAAACAAAGAAACAAAAAAGGUAGGGUAAUUAUUUUUUACGUAAUCCAGGAUUGGUGAAGUCCUUUAAUAGCAUACUGGGUUGCUGGAUUUUAGGACAUAAAAAUAAAAUUCUGUACAGGGGAAAAAAUCAAACAAAGUUAAAAGAGAAACAGACUAGUAAAACUUAUUUGUAUACUUCACAAAGGGCUAAGUUCCUCUUAAUACAAAGAACUAGAAAAUAAUCCAGUAGAAAAAUUAGCAAAGAGAAUUCAUAUGAAAAAAUGUACAACUUUAUUUAUAAUAUAAUAAAGAUGUAAAUUCAAGCUACAACAUACUCUUUGUCACCUAUCAAAUGAGCAAAGGUUAUGUAUAGUAUAACUCGGGAAAGGUGAGAAGAGAAAAUGGUCAGCCUUAUACAUUGCUGGUGGGAUUAUAAAGUAUUCAUACUCUAUAGAAAGCAGUUUGAAAAUGGUUUUCAAAAAUUAAAACACAGAUUUAUUUCGUUCUAGUAAUUCCAUUAUAGGAUUUUAUUCUCUAGAAGAUUUUGCAUAUAUGUCAAAUAAAUAUCUAAGAAUAUUUGUGGCAGCAUUAUUUGUUACUGCAAAAGAUUGGAAACAUGCUAAACAUAUCAGUAGGGAAGUAGUUAGGUGAAUUAUGGUGUAUAUAUUCAACAGAAUACUAGUCAGCCUUUAAAAAUAAUGAGAGAAUACUAUGUGUACUGCUGUGGUGCUAUGUCAAAGAUAUGAGGAAAAAAAGCAAGAGGCAUGACUGCAUGUGCAGUUUGCUGCCAUUCGUGUGGUUAAAAUAUAUAUUUUUAUAUGCUAUAUAUGCCUAUGUAUUAGAAUAAAAUUCUUUAUUAUAAUAAAAUCCAUAUGUGUGUGUGUGUGUGUGUGUGUGUGUGUGUGUGUAUAUAUAGGCAGCUAUAGAAUGUAAUGUGCAUGGGAGGAUACGGGAGAGUCUGAUGACAGUAAUUGCUCCAGUGUGUAGAAGUGGUUGCCUAGAGGACAAAGAUGGACUAACUUUUAAAGUAUACUGUUUGGUAAUUUUUCAGUAUUUUAAAAUCAUGUGCAUGUAAUACUAUUCAAAGUUAAUAUUUUUAAGUUAUGUUUUGCUUACAGGAAUUGGUAAGAAGGAAAAAAUAAGAGACCAUAAUAGUUGUUACAAACAAAUGAUUACUGCAAUACUGUUUUUAACUUUAGUUAUUGUUAGAGAUCUUCUAAUUCAAAGUUUUCAGUUGAUGUUACAUGGCUCACAGAAGGGUAGUCCUAGUAGAAUGGGGGCUGAAGGAAGGCGUUGGGGUUCCUGUGAACAAAUAGCAUGGUGAGUGACAACCAACAGUUAAAAGCAGCAUACUGCUCCUUUUGAUAUUUUAAGUGCAUUAAAUGAGGUGUGCCUUACUACUUGGAAUCUACUUCAGCAGCCAGCCACAGUGUACAGCUGCCUUUUGUGGGAAAGGGAUCAUGGAAUUGUUACUGGAGUUUGUAUUCACGGUGCCGAAGGAACAUGCCACCUACCACAAGGUGCAACCCACUUACAAUGAGAGGACAAGGAAGCAGGGAGGGUGUCUCUGGUGGCCCAGCUCCAGGCCUGACUAUCUGUAUUCACCUGUAUUGGAUGCUGCUCACCACGUGCGUUUGAUAUGCUCUGCAAGAAUAAAACCCAAGACAAGCCACAUAAAAGCAACCUAAAAAUUAAACUGUCAUCAUAUUAUUUGUUUUAAAACUAUGGAAUAAUAUAUCUGAGGAAGAUUUCUCUCAAAAUUGUUUUUCUCAAUUUCAAGUCAGAAGACAUGUCUUCAUCUACAUGGCAUCUUUCCUUACCUCUAUGUGCCAUACGAUGGUUAUGGACAGCAGCCAGAAAGCUAUCUUUCUCAGAUGGCAUUCAGUAUCGACAGAGCACUUAAUGUGGCUUUAGGCAAUCCAUCUUCCACUGCUCAGCAUGUGUUCAAAGUGUCAUUAGUAUCAGGAAUGCCUUUUUAUGGUUAUCAUGAGAAGGAAAGACACUUUAUGAAGAUCUAUCUUUACAAUCCUACAAUGGUGAAAAGGAUAUGUGAACUUUUGCAAAGCGGAGCCAUAAUGAAUAAAUUUUACCAGCCUCAUGAAGCGCAUAUUCCCUACCUCCUACAGCUCUUCAUUGACUACAAUCUUUAUGGCAUGAAUUUAAUAAAUCUGGCUGCUGUCAAGUUCCGAAAAGCAAGAAGGAAAAGUAAUACAUUGCAUGCAACUGGAUCCUGCAAGAAUCAUUUAUCAGGAAAUUCUCUUGCUGAUACUUUAUUUCGGUGGGAACAAGAUGAAAUACCAAGCUCUUUAAUAUUGGAAGGUGUUGAACCACAGAGUACAUGUGAAUUAGAAGUGGAUGCUGUAGCUGCUGAUAUCUUAAAUCGUCUGGACAUUGAAGCUCAAAUUGGUGGAAACCCUGGUCUACAGGCCAUAUGGGAAGAUGAAAAGCAACGGCGAAGAAACAGAAAUGAAACUUCUCAAAUGAGCCAACCUGAGUCACAAGAUCACAGGUUUGUGCCAGCAACAGAAAGUGAAAAAAAAUUUCAGAAGAGACUUCAGGAAAUUCUCAAACAGAAUGAUUUCUCUGUCAGAACAUUAUCAGGAUCUGUGGACUACAGCGAUGGAUCCCAGGAGUUCUCUGCUGAGUUAACAUUGCACUCUGAGGUUCUGUCUCCUGAAAUGCUUCAGUGUACACCAGCCAAUAUGGUAGAAGUUCACAAAGACAAAGAGUCAAGCAAAGGUCACACUAGACACAAAGUGGAAGAAGCUCUUAUUAAUGAAGAAGCAAUUUUGAACCUUAUGGAAAAUAGUCAGACUUUUCAGCCUUUGACCCAAAGACUGAGUGAGUCACCUGUUUUCAUGGACAGUAGUCCUGAUGAGGCUCUGGUACAUCUUCUUGCUGGUUUGGAAAGUGAUGGAUAUCGGGGGGAAAGAAAUAGGAUGCCAUCACCAUGUCGCUCCUUUGGAAAUAAUAAAUAUCCACAAAAUAGUGAUGAUGAAGAAAAUGAACCACAGAUUGAAAAAGAGGAAAUGGAGCUUAGUUUGGUGAUGUCCCAGAGAUGGGACAGCAAUAUUGAAGAACAUUGUGCCAAAAAGAGAUCACUGUGCAGAAAUACCCACAGAAGUUCAACUGAAGAUGAUGACUCAUCUUCAGGAGAAGAAAUGGAAUGGAGUGAUAACAGUUUGCUUCUAGCCAGUCUUUCUAUACCUCAGUUAGAUGGAACUGCAGAUGAAAAUAGUGACAAUCCAUUGAACAAUGAAAAUUCUAGAACCCACUCUUCUGUAAUUGCAACAAGCAAGCUUUCAGUUAAACCCUCCAUCUUUCACAAAGAUGCUGCUACAUUAGAACCCUCAUCUUCUGCUAAGAUUACCUUUCAGUGUAAACACACAAGUGCCCUUUCUUCCCAUGUUUUGAACAAGGAAGAUUUAAUUGAAGACCUUUCACAGACAAACAAAAAUACAGAAAAAGGUCUAGAUAACUCAGUCACUUCUUUUACAAACGAAAGCACUUAUUCUAUGAAAUACCCUGGAUCUUUAAGCAGUACUGUUCAUUCAGAAAAUUCUCAUAAAGAGAAUAGUAAGAAAGAGAUCCUCCCAGUAUCUUCCUGUGAAAGUAGUAUUUUUGAUUAUGAAGAAGAUAUUCCAUCUGUUACAAGACAAGUACCAAGUAGAAAAUAUACAAACAUUAGAAAAAUCGAAAAGGAUUCCCCUUUUAUACAUAUGCACCGUCACCCUAACGAGAAUACAUUGGGCAAAAAUUCUUUCAACUUUUCUGACUUAAAUCAUUCAAAAAAUAAAGUAUCCUCUGAAGGAAAUGAAAAAGGAAACAGCACAGCUCUGAGUAGUUUAUUCCCUUCAUCAUUUACUGAAAAUUGUGAAUUACUGUCAUGCUCAGGGGAGAAUAGAACUAUGGUGCAUUCUCUUAAUAGCACUGCUGAUGAAAGUGGACUAAAUAAACUUAAAAUUAGGUAUGAAGAAUUUCAAGAACAUAAAACAGAAAAGCCAAGCCUCAGCCAGCAAGCAGCACACUAUAUGUUUUUUCCCAGUGUUGUUCUUUCUAACUGUCUUACUAGACCACAGAAACUAUCUCCUGUCACAUAUAAAUUACAACCUGGCAAUAAACCAUCCCGGUUAAAAUUGAAUAAAAGGAAACUUGCAGGUCAUCAGGAGACUUCUACCAAAAGUAGUGAGACUGGAUCCACAAAAGAUAAUUUUAUACAAAAUAAUCCUUGUAAUAGUAAUCCUGAGAAGGAUAAUGCAUUGGCUAGUGAUUUAACUAAAACCACUCGUGGAGCUUUUGAAAAUAAAACACCCACAGAUGGUUUUAUAGACUGUCACUUUGGAGAUGGAACGUUAGAAACUGAGCAGUCCUUUGGACUAUAUGGAAAUAAAUACACACUUAGAGCCAAACGCAAGGUAAAUUAUGAGACUGAAGACAGUGAGUCAAGUUUUGUAACUCACAACUCAAAAAUUAGUCUACCUCAUCCCAUGGAAAUUGGUGAAAGUUUAGAUGGAACUCUCAAAUCCCGAAAACGAAGAAAAAUGUCUAAAAAGCUGCCCCCUGUCAUCAUAAAGUAUAUUAUUAUUAAUAGAUUUAGAGGGAGAAAAAAUAUGCUUGUGAAGCUAGGAAAAAUAGACUCUAAAGAAAAACAAGUAAUAUUAACAGAAGAAAAAAUGGAACUAUAUAAAAAGCUUGCACCUUUGAAGGACUUUUGGCCAAAAGUUCCCGACUCCCCUGCAACCAAAUAUCCCAUUUAUCCACUAACACCAAAGAAAAGUCACAGAAGAAAGUCAAAACAUAAAUCUGCUAAGAAAAAAACUGGUAAACAACAAAGGACAAAUAAUGAAAAUAUUAAAAGAACUUUGUCUUUCAGGAAAAAACGGUCACAUGCUAUUCUUUCUCCUCCCUCACCAUCUUACAAUGCUGAAACCGAAGAUUGUGACCUGAAUUAUAGUGAUGUUAUGUCUAAACUAGGUUUUCUUUCUGAGAGAAGCACAAGUCCCAUAAAUUCUUCUCCACCUCGCUGCUGGUCUCCCACAGAUCCAAGAGCUGAAGAAAUCAUGGCUGCUGCAGAAAAAGAGGCAAUGCUUUUUAAGGGUCCUAAUGUAUAUAAGAAGACUGUUAAUUCUCGUAUAGGAAAAACUAGUCGCGCAAGAGCACAGAUUAAGAAAUCAAAAGCAAAGCUUGCUAAUCCCUCUAUAGUUACUAAGAAAAGGAACAAACGAAAUCAGACAAAUAAACUAGUAGAUGAUGGAAAAAAGAAACCAAGAGCAAAACAAAAAACAAAUGAGAAAGGUACAUCGAGAAAGCAUACAACACUUAAGGAUGAAAAAAUAAAAUCUCAGUCUGGUGCUGAGGUUAAGUUUGUACUGAAACACCAGAAUGUGUCUGAAUUUGCAAGUAGUUCUGGAGGCUCUCAACUACUUUUUAAACAGAAAGAUAUGCCACUAAUGGGCUCUGCUGUAGAUCAUCCCCUUUCUGCUUCCCUACCCACUGGAAUUAAUGCACAACAGAAGUUAUCUGGCUGCUUUUCUUCUUUCUUAGAAAGCAAGAAGUCUGUAGAUUUGCAGACAUUCCCCAGUUCACGAGAUGAUUUGCAUCCAUCAGUUGUUUGUAAUUCUAUAGGACCUGGAGUCUCAAAAAUUAAUGUUCAAAGGCCUCAUAAUCAAAGUGCUAUGUUUACUCUAAAGGAAUCAACGUUAAUUCAAAAAAAUAUAUUUGACCUUUCCAAUCAUUUAUCUCAGGUAGCACAGAAUACACAGAUAUCUUCUGGUAUGUCCUCAAAGAUAGAAGAUAAUGCAAAUAAUAUACAAAGAAACUAUUUGUCAUCAAUCGGAAAGUUAAGUGAAUAUCGCAAUUCCCUAGAAUCAAAGCUGGACCAAGCAUAUACCCCUAAUUUUUUGCAUUGCAAAGACAGUCAGCAGCAGAUUGUGUGCAUAGCGGAACAGUCAAAGCACAGUGAAACUUGUUCUCCGGGAAAUACAGCUUCAGAGGAAAGCCAAAUGCCUAAUAAUUGCUUUGUAACUUCCUUGAGAAGUCCAAUCAAACAAAUAGCAUGGGAGCAAAAGCAAAGGGGCUUUAUUUUAGAUAUGUCAAAUUUUAAACCUGAAAGAGUAAAACCGAGGUCGUUAUCAGAAGCAAUUUCACAAACCAAAGCACUUUCUCAGUGUAAAAAUCGAAAUGUGUCAACACCUUCAGCAUUUGGUGAAGGACAGUCUGGACUGGCAGUUCUAAAAGAAUUGUUACAAAAAAGACAGCAGAAAGCACAAAAUGCAAAUACUACACAAGACCCAUUAUCCAAUAAACAUCAACCAAAUAAAAAUAUUUCUGGUUCCCUUGAGCAUAACAAAGCAAAUAAACGGACACGAUCGGUAACGUCCCCAAGAAAACCUCGAACUCCCAGAAGUACAAAACAAAAAGAAAAAAUCCCCAAACUUCUCAAAGUAGACUCUUUAAAUUUACAAAACUCUAGCCAGUUGGAUAACUCUGUAUCAGAUGAUAGUCCCAUCUUUUUUUCAGAUCCAGGCUUUGAAAGUUGUUACUCACUUGAAGAUAGUUUAUCUCCUGAACAUAAUUAUAAUUUUGAUAUUAACACAAUAGGUCAGACUGGAUUUUGUAGCUUUUAUUCUGGAAGUCAGUUUGUCCCAGCUGAUCAGAAUUUGCCUCAGAAGUUCCUAAGUGAUGCUGUUCAGGAUCUUUUUCCAGGACAAGCUAUAGAAAAAAAUGAGUUUUUAAGUCAUGACAACCAGAAAUGUGAUGAAGACAAGCAUCAUACCACAGACUCAGCCUCAUGGAUUAGAUCUGGUACUUUAAGUCCUGAAAUUUUUGAGAAGUCAACCAUAGAUAGCAAUGAGAAUCGUCGCCACAACCAGUGGAAAAAUAGCUUUCAUCCUCUAACAACUCGGUCUAACUCAAUAAUGGAUUCUUUCUGUGUUCAGCAGGCAGAAGACUGUCUAAGUGAAAAAUCUAGAUUGAAUAGGAGUUCAGUAAGCAAAGAAGUGUUUCUUAGCCUCCCACAGCCAAACAAUUCAGACUGGAUUCAAGGUCACACCAGAAAAGAAAUGGGACAGUCUCUUGACUCAGCCAAUACCUCUUUUACUGCAAUACUCUCCUCCCCUGAUGGUGAACUUGUAGACGUGGCCUGUGAAGAUUUAGAACUGUAUGUUUCAAGAAACAAUGAUAUGUUGACACCAACUCCUGAUAGUUCACCAAGAUCUACUAGCUCUCCUUCACAAUCUAAAAAUGGCAGCUUCACCCCUCGAACUGCUAACAUUCUGAAACCACUUAUGUCCCCCCCAAGUAGGGAAGAAAUUAUGGCAACUUUGUUGGAUCAUGACCUGUCUGAGACUAUUUACCAGGAACCAUUUUGCAGUAAUCCUUCUGAUGUACCAGAAAAGCCCAGGGAGAUUGGUGGACGGCUCCUCAUGGUAGAAACUCGACUUGCAAAUGAUCUGGCUGAGUUUGAGGGAGACUUUUCCUUGGAAGGACUUCGUCUUUGGAAAACAGCAUUCUCAGCAAUGACUCAGAAUCCAAGGCCAGGGUCACCCCUUCGCAGUGGCCAAGGAGUUGUCAAUAAAGGGUCAAGUAAUAGCCCUAAGAUGGUUGAAGAUAAAAAAAUUGUGAUUAUGCCUUGCAAAUGUGCCCCAAGUCGACAACUGGUUCAAGUGUGGCUUCAAGCCAAAGAAGAAUACGAACGUUCCAAGAAACUGCCUAAAACCAAGCCAACUGGAGUUGUAAAAUCUGCUGAGAACUUUAGCUCUUCAGUUAACCCAGAUGACAAACCUGUAGUGCCUCCAAAAAUGGAUGUAAGUCCAUGUAUACUCCCCACUACAGCACAUACCAAGGAGGAUGUUGAUAAUUCUCAGAUUGCUUUACAAGCACCAACCACGGGAUGUAGUCAAACUGCAAGUGAAAGUCAGAUGCUGCCACCAGUUGCCUCUGCAAGUGAUCCCGAAAAAGAUGAAGAUGAUGAUGAUAACUAUUACAUUAGUUAUAGCUCCCCUGAUUCUCCAGUAAUUCCCCCUUGGCAACAACCAAUAUCCCCAGAUUCCAAAGCAUUAAAUGGAGAUGAUAGACCCUCAUCACCAGUAGAGGAGCUGCCUUCAUUGGCUUUUGAGAACUUCUUAAAGCCAAUAAAAGAUGGUAUACAAAAAAGCCCCUGCAGUGAGCCUCAAGAGCCUCUAGUGAUAUCUCCAAUUAAUACUAGGGCAAGAACUGGGAAAUGUGAAUCACUUUGCUUUCAUAGUACACCAAUCAUACAGAGAAAACUUCUGGAAAGGCUUCCUGAAGCACCUGGCCUUAGCCCAUUAUCAACAGAACCAAAAACACAGAAGUUGAGUAAUAAGAAAGGAAGUAAUACUGACACUCUUAGAAGAGUACUGUUAACACAAGCAAAGAAUCAAUUUGCAGCAGUAAAUACCCCACAGAAAGAAACUUCUCAGAUUGAUGGACCAUCUUUAAACAAUACUUACGGUUUCAAAGUCAGCAUACAAAACUUACAGGAGGCAAAAGCUUUACAUGAGAUACAAAAUCUUACCCUAAUCAGUGUGGAGUUGCAUGCUCGAACUAGACGAGACUUAGAACCGGAUCCUGAAUUUGACCCAAUCUGUGCUCUGUUCUACUGCAUCUCAUCUGACACUCCACUGCCAGAUACAGAAAAAACAGAACUCACAGGUGUAAUAGUGAUUGAUAAAGACAAGACAGUUUUCAGUCAAGAUAUCAGAUAUCAGACUCCAUUACUUAUUAGAUCUGGAAUUACAGGACUCGAAGUCACCUAUGCUGCUGAUGAGAAGGCACUUUUUCAUGAAAUUGCAAAUAUAAUAAAGAGAGGUUGUCAUCAACAUGUCAGAUGCUUUCAGUAUCCACACUUCUUUUAUUUCUGCAAGCAACUCAGAGAAAGAAAUAUGUAUGAUCCUGAUAUUCUGCUAGGAUAUGAGAUUCAGAUGCAUUCCUGGGGUUACCUCUUACAAAGGGCUGCCGCUUUAAGUAUUGACUUAUGUCGGAUGAUCUCUCGGGUGCCAGAUGACAAAAUUGAGAACAGAUUUGCAGCUGAAAGAGAUGAGUAUGGAUCAUAUACAAUGAGUGAGAUAAAUAUUGUUGGCCGAAUUACACUAAAUCUUUGGAGAAUCAUGAGAAAUGAGGUGGCUCUAACUAACUACACCUUUGAAAAUGUGAGCUUUCAUGUUCUUCAUCAGCGUUUUCCCCUCUUUACCUUUCGAGUCUUGUCAGACUGGUUUGAUAACAAGACAGAUCUAUACAGAUGGAAAAUGGUUGAUCAUUAUGUUAGCCGUGUCCGUGGAAAUCUCCAAAUGUUAGAACAGCUGGACCUGAUUGGGAAAACCAGUGAGAUGGCUAGACUUUUUGGCAUUCAGUUUUUACAUGUACUGACAAGGGGUUCACAGUACCGUGUGGAAUCAAUGAUGUUGCGUAUUGCUAAACCAAUGAACUAUAUUCCUGUGACACCUAGUGUUCAGCAAAGAUCCCAGAUGAGAGCCCCACAGUGUGUUCCUCUAAUUAUGGAGCCUGAAUCCCGCUUCUAUAGCAACUCUGUUCUCGUUUUGGAUUUCCAAUCACUUUAUCCUUCUAUUGUGAUUGCAUAUAACUACUGCUUUUCCACCUGCCUUGGCCAUGUGGAGAACUUGGGAAAGUAUGAUGAGUUCAAAUUUGGCUGUACCUCUCUGAGAGUACCUCCAGAUUUACUUUACCAAGUUAGGCAUGAUAUCACAGUGUCCCCCAAUGGAGUAGCUUUUGUCAAGCCUUCAGUAAGAAAAGGUGUACUACCAAGAAUGCUUGAAGAAAUUUUGAAGACUAGAUUUAUGGUGAAGCAGUCAAUGAAGGCUUACAAGCAAGACAGAGCCCUGUCACGAAUGCUUGAUGCGCGUCAGUUGGGACUUAAGCUGAUAGCAAAUGUCACAUUUGGCUAUACAUCUGCUAAUUUUUCUGGGAGAAUGCCAUGCAUUGAGGUUGGCGAUAGUAUUGUUCACAAAGCCAGAGAGACCUUGGAACGAGCUAUUAAACUGGUGAAUGAUACCAAGAAAUGGGGGGCUAGGGUUGUAUAUGGCGAUACUGACAGUAUGUUUGUGCUACUGAAAGGAGCCACUAAGGAGCAGUCUUUUAAGAUUGGUCAGGAAAUUGCCGAAGCUGUAACUGCUACCAAUCCUAAACCAGUGAAAUUGAAGUUUGAAAAGGUAUAUUUGCCCUGUGUUUUACAAACAAAAAAGAGGUAUGUGGGUUACAUGUAUGAAACACUGGAUCAGAAGGACCCAGUAUUUGAUGCAAAAGGAAUAGAAACAGUCAGAAGAGAUUCCUGCCCUGCUGUUUCUAAGAUACUUGAGCGUUCUCUAAAGCUGCUAUUUGAAACGAGAGAUAUAAGUCUAAUUAAACAGUAUGUUCAGCGACAAUGUAUGAAGCUUCUGGAAGGAAAGGCCAGCAUACAAGACUUUAUCUUUGCCAAGGAAUACAGAGGAAGUUUUUCUUAUAAACCAGGAGCUUGUGUGCCAGCCCUUGAACUUACAAGGAAAAUGCUGACUUAUGACCGGCGCUCUGAGCCUCAGGUUGGGGAGCGAGUGCCAUACGUCAUCAUUUAUGGGACCCCCGGAGUACCACUUAUCCAGCUUGUAAGGCGCCCAGUGGAAGUCCUGCAGGACCCAACUCUGAGACUGAAUGCUACUUACUAUAUUACCAAGCAAAUCCUUCCACCCUUGGCAAGAAUCUUCUCACUUAUUGGUAUUGAUGUCUUCAGCUGGUAUCAUGAAUUACCAAGGAUCCAUAAAGCUACCAGCUCCUCGCGAAGUGAACCUGAAGGGCGGAAAGGCACUAUUUCACAAUAUUUUACUACCUUACACUGUCCUGUGUGUGAUGACCUAACUCAGCAUGGCAUCUGUAGUAAAUGUCGGAGCCAACCUCAGCAUGUUGCAGUCAUCCUCAACCAAGAAAUCCGGGAGUUGGAACGUCAACAGGAGCAACUUGUAAAGAUAUGCAAGAACUGUACAGGUUGCUUUGAUCGACACAUCCCAUGUGUUUCUCUGAACUGCCCAGUACUUUUCAAACUCUCCCGAGUAAAUAGAGAAUUGUCCAAGGCACCAUAUCUCCGGCAGUUAUUAGACCAGUUUUAAAUUGUCAAUAUCACAGUAUUACAGGUGCUAUUUUUUUCAGUGCUUACCACUAAACUGUUGUGCAUGGUGCUUUUUAACUUUCAUCGAGUCAAGGAUGUUCACUGUCUGUUAUCUGAAGACUAUGAAGACUUCUAUGCUAACCGAAUUAAAAUGUACUUGUUGAUCUCUGAAUAGCUCACUUCUUACAAUGUACAAAUUCCUCAUUCUGUCACCUUUUAAACAUUGUUUUAUAAUGCAGGUGUUGGAUUUGCUCCAGUAUGUGUACCAUCUUGUAAAUUCAUUUGAGUAGAUCAUGUUUACUUCCCAGUGGAAGGAGCACUGAAAACCUCUUAAAGAAAAAGCAUUUGUGUGUUUUCCUUGAACUGUCUGUAUCAAGACGUGUUACUUCGAGAUAUCCAUUCACUUUAUAAUUUUGACUGCAAAAUAUUUUGUAAAUACACUUUUUUACUUUUCAAACGAGCAAAAUAAUGUGCAAUGAUUUUUAUACAAAUGAUUUUCAAGUUGUUUGGUAUAUUUCCUCUAGGUUUUGCUUGACUCAAAGUAGAUCGUUAUUUUGAUCAAACUGUGCAAACAGUAGUACCACGUGUAGCAUUUUGAAACAUUAUUUUUUUUUAAAAAAUGCUGUCUUGCUUUAGCUAUUAAUGGGGCAUUGUGAGGAACUGUGCAAAGACAUUUUUGUUACAAACCUGUGGGCCUGUUGCAAUACUUUAAAAAUAAAAAAUUUUAUUCCAUUUGCUUGUUUUGUAUAGACAUUUCUAUUGCUUCUAAAUAUACUUAAAAUAUUUUCUUUCCUUAUGUACUGUACAGUUAAUCUUAUUUGCCAUCAUCUUGAACACAAAAUGUGUAUUUAGAAUAUUUGUAUAACUGUGUAAAAUAAAAAAGGAAUUAUGUGGUCAGUGCAUUGUUUUUUAAACUGGAAAUCAUUUUGUUUUAAAAGUUAAUAAUGGAAACCAUAUUAAAAUUGAAUAAAAUAUAAAAUAAUA